GCUGCUCUCGGCUGCCGUCGGGGUGGCUGGCUGCUUCAGCGCCGAGCUCUCCGACAGCCGCCGCCUCUUGGCGCCGGGCGGCGAGGGCCCCUUGGCCCGCUCCCCGGCGCGGUGCGACCCGGCCGCGGGCUCCGCGUGCCCCGCCGGGUGGAGCAGCAGACAGCGGUCCAGGUGCGAGUUGAUGUGCGCGGCGGGCAUCAUCUGCUGGCACACGGGGCACUGCACCUGGUGCAGCUGCGAAAGGAAGGGGUCGUCUUCCGGCCCGCUCACCUCCAUGGCGGCCGCCGCCCUCCCCGGCGCCCGGCGCGGCCGCAGCAACCCGUGCGCACGCGGAGGCCUUCGAUGCCCUCCGCUAGGCCCCGCGCCGCGAGACCCUCGCUCGGGGAACCAGCAGGACGCUCGCGGGCCGGAGGAGGGCGCCGCUCAUGCCUCACGUCCGCAGCUCCCGCGUCCGCCCGCCCUCGGCCGGCCGCUGGCAGCGCCUCACGCGGCGUGUCGGGAAGUGUAGUUCGUGGCCGUUUGCCCCGGCGGCGGAGGCGCCUCGCGCGGCAUGUAAUCAAGAGAAAGAAGCACUGAAGAGUCAUAAUUGUGUCCUGAUUUAUAAAUCGGAGACAGAGGGAGACGAAAACCACACUCCAGAAAGUAGCUUAAUCGGACUCACUACUAAGAUGUUAAAAGUGAAGAGGCUGGAAGAAUUCAACACGUGUUAUAACAGCAACCAGCUGGAGAAAAUGGCCUUUUUUCAGUGCAGGGAAGAGGUGGAGAAAGUGAAGUGUUUUCUGGAAAAAAAUUCUGGGGACCAGGAUUCAAGAUCUGGACAUAAUGAGGCGAAGGAGGUGUGGUCAAACGCCGACCUGACGGAAAGGAUGCCCGUCAAAAGCAAAAGGACAUCAGCCCUCGCAGUUGACAUCCCGGCUCCUCCGGCCCCAUUUGAUCAUCGUAUUGUGACAGCCAAGCAAGGAGCGGUCAACAGCUUCUAUACUGUGAGCAAGACAGAAAUCCUAGGAGGAGGGCGUUUCGGCCAGGUUCACAAGUGUGAGGAGACGGCCACAGGUCUGAAGCUGGCAGCCAAAAUCAUCAAGACCAGAGGCAUGAAGGACAAGGAGGAGGUGAAGAACGAGAUCAGCGUCAUGAACCAGCUGGACCACGCGAACCUCAUCCAGCUGUACGAUGCCUUCGAGUCUAAGAACGACAUUGUCCUGGUCAUGGAGUAUGUGGAUGGUGGGGAGCUGUUUGACCGCAUCAUCGAUGAGAGCUACAAUUUGACGGAGCUUGAUACCAUCCUGUUCAUGAAGCAGAUAUGUGAGGGGAUAAGGCACAUGCAUCAGAUGUACAUUCUCCACUUGGACCUGAAGCCUGAGAAUAUCCUGUGUGUGAAUCGGGAUGCUAAGCAAAUAAAAAUUAUUGAUUUUGGAUUGGCCAGAAGAUACAAACCCAGAGAGAAGCUGAAGGUGAACUUUGGAACCCCAGAAUUUCUCGCCCCUGAAGUUGUGAACUAUGAUUUUGUUUCAUUUCCCACUGACAUGUGGAGUGUGGGGGUCAUCGCCUAUAUGCUACUUAGCGGUUUGUCGCCUUUCCUGGGUGACAAUGAUGCUGAGACGCUGAACAACAUCCUGGCCUGCAGGUGGGACUUAGAGGAUGAAGAAUUUCAGGACAUCUCGGAGGAGGCCAAGGAGUUCAUCUCUAAGCUUCUGAUUAAGGAGAAGAGUUGGCGAAUAAGUGCAAGCGAAGCUCUCAAGCACCCCUGGUUGUCAGACCACAAGCUCCACUCCAGACUCAAUGCCCAGAAGAAGAAGAAUCGUGGCUCUGAUGCCCAGGACUUUGUGACCAAAUAGUCUACAGGAGGCAGCCAUUUGGAAGGAAAACUGCUGUGGUUGCUGCUGCUUCGAGAAAAUUUUUUGAAAAAUCAGCAGUUCUGAUGCCUUGACCCCUGUGAUGACCUGGUAGUCUUAGCAGGGGGAGCCCUCGACCCUGAAUGUGAACUUGAACUGGAGUGCCUCUGCUGCGCUCAGAGGAACACCCAGCGCUGCGGUCUGGUCUCAGGGCGCAAACACAUCCCUGCACCCGGUGGUGGUGAUGUUGGGAAGAUGUUUCCCUGCCAUCUUGAGAUUUUUUACUUUUUUAAAAAAAUUUUUUGAUCUUAGUCACUGGGGCAGGGGGUGCAUUAUGUCUGCCAUUUCUCAAAUGACUACAGCUGUGACACUUAAGAUUGAUUGGAGAUUUUAAAACUGGAGGAUGCAUUUAGAGGGAGAAAGCUACUUCCAGCCAUUAGACUAUGCCUUUGGAAGGGGCAAUUAGAUGGCCAGAAAGAAUUCUGACUCCCAUGCACCCUUGGAGACUUAGUUUCACAGACUCUGUCAUUUUGAUUUGGUCUGUGGUCACGUGACUACAAUGGAUAAAUAAUUUGUUUGCUGGAACAGAAGCCGUCUUUGAAUUCUCCAACAAGAGGCAUCAGCCACUGUGUCUUUCAUUUAUUCUGAAUUGUCCCCAGCGUGCGUUUUCUUCCAUGUAGCUGAUUCUGUUUUUCACAUCUAUACUCCCUGCACCCUUCUGACUGACAGUUCAUCCCCACAAAACACAUUGGUUUUGAGAGGUGAUGCAAAAAGUAUCUGUUUAUGGUUGGACUUUGAAAUUCUGACCUUUGAAAUAAUGUCAACAGUCACAACAGGUUUCCUCAAGCCCCAUUUGUCAACUAAAAGAGACGGAUCUGCACCUCCUGGAGCAAGAUAGCACUGAGCUUUCAACAUUGAAGUGACUUGGGAAAUAACAUUCAAGCUUCUGGGUAAACACAUACAAACAGUGGCAAAGACCAAGUACAGUCUCUCGCCUGUGCUGUCUCAUGGGACUCAAUGGUGGUGAAGAAAUCUCAAUCGGACACCAGAGGUGGGGGCAACUCUGCAAGCUCACCUGCUGGACGUGAGAAUGUUGGAACGUUCCAGUUGGAAGGUUCCUAUGCCUAGCCUGUGUGCCAUUUCAUGGCAGAUAUGUAAGAAAGGAAAUGGCCCUACUGUAGACAGCUUAUGGGGCCCAGAAAGGCACUGGGCUUUAAAGAGCGAAAUGAGUGUGUCAUUUCCACAUGAAGGAGAGGCAAGGAAAAGCCCCACAAAAUUCCUGUUACCCGCUGAACUCCAAGCUCACCAACCAGAUUCAUGAGCUUUCUCACAUUUUCCAUUUCCAAAUAACUGUUGUGUUGAAUCAGCUGUGUUAAUGCCUUUAUUCUUUGUUUUUUUUUUUUAGACGGAGUCUCGCUCUGUCACGAGGCUGGAGUGCAGUGGCCCCAUCUCGGCUCACUGCAACCUCCGCCUCCCAGGUUCAAGCGAUUCUCCUGCAGCCUCCCGAGUAGCUGGGAUUACAGGCGCACGCCACCACGCACGGCUGAUUUUUGCAUUUUUAGUAGAGAUGGGGUUUCUCCAUGUUGGCCAGAAUGGUCUCAAUUACUGUUGUCGCAAUAGCAAUGAAAGGCAUAAGAAUUACUUGGUGGCCUCAUGAGGGAUGGCAGUUUCACUUUGCAUCAGCUUUCCCCCAUUAUCUCUCAGAUCCACUUAAGGAAUCCUUACAGCAUGCCGUGAAUGUGUGCAACAUCCUUAUUCUCAUCUUUAAGGUAAGGAGGAAGUAGAGAUAGAAGGAAAUACGUGAUUUGGUGAAGGCCACAUGCGAAUUUUGUGGUCGUGUUAGUUAUAAAACUGACUCCUUUCCAGCCUUUGCUCUUACAUUAUGAUGCGUUUCUUUUUCUCCUUUGGCCUUGCAUUUAUCCGAGGUUGGUUUCUUAUGUUCCUGUGAUGUGACUAUGCUUAAGUGUUUAAUUUAGUUUGCUUAAAACACACACACCACACACACACACACACACAAAACCCUGUGACUGGAGUGUUAUAUUACUAUGCUAUCUUUAGCUGAUGAUAUUCAUUGAGCCUGGAAAAAUACAAGCCAGUGCAUGCAUUAAUACUUAGUUAGACCGCAGAGAGCUGGCAUUCACUCAAAUGCUAAACAGGACACAGGGGUCUGAUUUGAAGCCCCUCGUGGCAGGGCGUUUUCUGUCCUGUGGUGUGCAUUCUCUACCAAAUCAAGCAGGAGAUCUUUUGCACGACGUGCAAUUUGCAUCCACCUUCCCUUCUGACUCAGGUUGGCAGAUAAACUGUCCCCAGACCCUGCCACACAUGGAAGAGACAGCUCAGGCCAAAUACAGGCAUGAUUUCUUUGCCAAGUUAAUGCACUGAUGACCCUGCAGUGAGUGGGUGUGAUUUUUGUUUUGUUUUGAGGUUUAGAAAGGAGACUGUACUUUGAAAAUGGAUCUUGUUUGAUUCUGUAGUUAAAUUUCCACAUUUGGAAUGGGAAGGCAUCUCCAUGCCAGCAGGGUGCCUUUUAUAUGAGUGCUGAGGGUAGUUUGCAUUGCAGAGUUCAUGAUUACAGUCUAGAGUUACUUGAAAUGGGAGAUUAUCAGUCUAGUGUUCAUCCCGCCCCUGCUCCAUGUCCUUGUGUGGCUGCUCCAGCGAGAGCUGGUAACUAGGUAGACUGCUGCUCUAAUGGGGAAAGGGGGCUUUGCAAAGCCGAGGAAUCAAGCCAGAUGCGAGCAUGGACUCAGAAAAGCUGAGUCUGGCUAGACCAGGGCUAUGGAGAUCAAUUUUUCCAACAGGUCAUUAGGAUUUGGGAGGCUGUAUUUCUCCUCCACCCUCUUAAUGGAUGGUAUGGCUUUGCUCACUCACUAGGCAGUUCCCACUUUCUUUAGCAAAUGGAGGAAAUUAAGCACCGAUGUAGCACUUCCCACUGCCUGGAGAGAAAUAAACCUCGCAAGUUAUUAAGGAGAAGGCAUGCCUCAUUGGUAAUUUGGAAGACACCAACACUUACCCAGAAUCUGUUGCUAUUUAAAAAUCAGGGAGAGGAGGGCACAUGUCCCCAUUUGCUACAUUACAAACUUUGGACGAGACUCUCAUCUGAACUAACUUGGGGAAACAAUUUCUAGGUUGAAGCUGGUAACACUCAUGUCUGUUGAGUGCCAUAAGUUUGUUUUCAGUUAUUUCCUCUAACUUGAUAUUAAUUUGCUUUCUUUCCUCAAAAAUGUAAGUAGGCAUGUUGCCAUUGUUGUGGCUUGCUUUGAUGUAUGUUUGGAAAGAUGUGUGAAUACUUAAUUUUUAUCCAUUUUAUGGAAAUUAGCUUAGCAAUUUUUUUUUCUCUUUUAAGAAUCAAAAUAUGGAUUUGAUACUAGGAACAGAAUCUGCUCUUUAUUUCAUUCCUUUUUUGUCUCUUCUGCUUCCUCUGCCCCUCCCCCAGCCACGCAGCACGGGUGCCAGUGUGCAUGCGUGUGCUGGGGGCCAAAUGACAGAACCCCGGUUGAAAGUCCGCUUGUAAAAGCACAAGUGAGAGGCAGCAUCAGGCCCCUGGAGGGCUGUGGUCCUCGGACUCGGUUCUUUCCUGUCCCCUGGCCGUCCUGUCAUCCCUGUGUGCUGCAGCAUCACCACGGCCUACUUCCCAAUAUCCACAAAGCUUCGCCUUUGCUUUUGCACUCUCUUUUACAUUUUUUUACUUCUUUCCUUUUUCUUAAGUUCGGAUCCAAGUUUGUCUUCUUAUCCAUCACCAUGCUCCCUGAAAGCCUUUUUGAGAUUAAGAAAUUUUCUUACCAGGAGGCAACUUUCCGUCUGUCCUAAAGGGAAGUGGGUGCUGGAUUUAUUAGAUAUUGGGUUCCUGGAUUAAGAUGACUUCCUCACAUAGCUUGGAGUCUGCAGUUUCUCAGUUAGAAGUGUUCUAUAUUUCUUUUUGCUCCAUUUUAGUGCGCUGUGCUUUGUAUAAGUGGUCUUUCUAUGGGCAGUUUCACCUUCCAUGAAGGCUUAUAACUCAACCACUACUACCCAUUCAGAAGAGCAGAAAGCAUCUGCUGUGUGAGCGUUCAUAUGUUACCUAAUGUGUAUUUUGCUGUCGUCUCAGCUGAUAGAUGUCAGUGAGUCUUUCUGACUAGGUUUAUUGGUGUUGAUAAGAAAUUAAAAAAAGGAUUCAUAACGUGGUGAUUGUGUCUAUCAUGUAUAUUUUAAAUUUCUGAACGUACUUUCAUUUAGCUGUUUUUCUUUGCUUUCUAAAGAUGUAUAACAAUCAUGUAUAUGUAUUAUAUUGAAGAAUAAACAUGGACCUUAUUUA